GGAGCUGUCGCCUAGCCGCUAUCGCAGAGUGGAGCGGGGCUGGGAGCAAAGCGCUGAGGGAGCUCGGUACGCCGCCGCCUCGCACCCGCAGCCUCGCGCCCGCCGCCGCCCGUCCCCAGGUGAGUGGGGUCGGCCGGGGGCUCAGGCGAGGUGAGCUUCGUCGCUUCGCAGCCGGUUUGCGGGAGCUGGACCGAUCCAAGAUGGCGUCACGGGGAGCGACCUGCAGGGGGACGGCCGCACCCCCUGCCCCUCCCCGGCCCGGCGGGCGCCUCCCCGCAGGCCUCACGCCCCCGGCUCCGAGUCUGCAUCCUCAAGGCCGUCUGGGCGUUGGCUUUGGUGCGGGGCUCCCCAGCCGCCCCGCUCGCGCUCGCUGCCCCCACCCCACGGCUCCUGGGGCCCUGGGCCCUCCGCGGCCCUCCCCGGCCGCCUUCGCCCCCGCGCGCCGCGGCCUCUUCGCUCACCCUCCCCCAUUUCCUGAAGGACAACGGCUCUAUUUUACUGGGGUCCGCCAUCGUCUCGUCCGCCGGUCCUGGCUCUUCUUGUAAGCCGAGAACCAUGGAGUCUGGCAGUACCGCCGCCAGUGAGGAGGCACGCAGCCUUCGAGAAUGUGAGCUCUACGUCCAGAAGCAUAACAUUCAAGCGCUGCUCAAAGAUUCUAUUGUGCAGUUGUGCACUGCUCGACCUGAGAGACCCAUGGCAUUCCUCAGGGAAUACUUUGAGAGGUUGGAGAAGGAGGAGGCAAAACAGAUUCAGAAUCUGCAGAAAGCAGGCACUCGUACAGACUCAAGGGAGGAUGAGAUUUCUCCUCCUCCACCCAACCCAGUGGUUAAAGGUAGGAGGCGACGAGGUGCUAUCAGCGCUGAGGUCUACACGGAGGAAGAUGCGGCAUCCUAUGUUAGAAAGGUUAUACCAAAAGAUUACAAGACAAUGGCCGCUUUAGCCAAAGCCAUUGAAAAGAAUGUGCUGUUUUCACAUCUUGAUGAUAAUGAGAGAAGUGAUAUUUUUGAUGCCAUGUUUUCGGUCUCCUUUAUCGCAGGAGAGACUGUGAUUCAGCAAGGUGAUGAAGGGGAUAACUUCUAUGUGAUUGAUCAAGGAGAGACGGAUGUCUAUGUUAACAAUGAAUGGGCAACCAGUGUUGGGGAAGGAGGGAGCUUUGGAGAACUUGCUUUGAUUUAUGGAACACCGAGAGCAGCCACUGUCAAAGCAAAGACAAAUGUGAAAUUGUGGGGCAUCGACCGAGACAGCUAUAGAAGAAUCCUCAUGGGAAGCACACUGAGAAAGCGGAAGAUGUAUGAGGAAUUCCUUAGUAAAGUCUCUAUUUUAGAGUCUCUGGACAAGUGGGAACGUCUUACGGUAGCUGAUGCAUUGGAACCAGUGCAGUUUGAAGAUGGGCAGAAGAUUGUGGUGCAGGGAGAACCAGGGGAUGAGUUCUUCAUUAUUUUAGAGGGGUCAGCUGCUGUGCUACAACGUCGGUCAGAAAAUGAAGAGUUUGUUGAAGUGGGAAGAUUGGGGCCUUCUGAUUAUUUUGGUGAAAUUGCACUACUGAUGAAUCGUCCUCGUGCUGCCACAGUUGUUGCUCGUGGCCCCUUGAAGUGCGUUAAGCUGGACCGACCUAGAUUUGAACGUGUUCUUGGCCCAUGCUCAGACAUCCUCAAACGAAACAUCCAGCAGUACAACAGUUUUGUGUCACUGUCUGUCUGAAAUCUGCCUCCUGUGCCUCCCUUUUCUCCUCUCCCCAAUCCAUGCUUCACUCAUGCAAACUGCUUUAUUUUCCCUACUUGCAGCGCCAAGUGGCCACUGGCAUCGCAGCUUCCUGUCUGUUUAUAUAUUGAAAGUUGCUUUUAUUGCACCAUUUUCAAUUUGGAGCAUUAACUAAAUGCUCAUACACAGUUAAAUAAAUAGAAAGAGUUCUAUGGAGACUUUGCUGUUACUGCUUCUCUUUGUGCAGUGUUAGUAUUCACCCUGGGCAGUGAGUGCCAUGCUUUUUGGUGAGGGCAGAUCCCAGCACCUAUUGAAUUACCAUAGAGUAAUGAUGUAACAGUGCAAGAUUUUUUUUUUAAGUGACAUAAUUGUCCAGUUAUAAGCGUAUUUAGACUGUGGCCAUAUAUGCUGUAUUUCUUUGUAGAAUAAAUGGUUUCUCAUUAAACUCUAAAGAUUAGGGAAAAUGGAUAUAGAAAAUCUUAGUAUAGUAGAAAGACAUCUGCCUGUAAUUAAACUAGUUUAAGGGUGGAAAAAUGCCCAUUUUUGCUAAUUAUCAAUGGGAUAUGAUUGGUUCAGUUUUUUUUUUUCCAGAGUUGUUGUUUGCCAAGCUAAUCUGCCUGGUUUUAUUUAUAUCUUGUUAUUAAUGUUUCUUCUCCAAUUCUGAAAUACUUUUGAGUAUGGCUAUCUAUACCUGCCUUUUAAGUUUGAAACUAACUCAUAGAUUGCAAAUAUUGGUUAGUAUUUAACUACAUCUGCCUCGGCUCACAAAUUCCGAUUAGACCUUUAUCCAGCUAGUGCCAAAUAAUUGAUCAGAUGCUGAAUUGAGAAUAAGAAUUUGAGGUCUACAUUCUUGGUUGUUAAUUUAGAGCGUUUGGUUAAAGUAUGUCCUUCAGCUGACUCCAGUAUAAUCUCCUCUGCUCAUUAAACUGAUUCCAGGAGAUUGGAUUUGCUGUGACUAGAUACAGAUGGAGCAAAUGUCCUAACAGAGAAAUAGAGGUGAUGCUGCUAAAGGGAGAAAUGCCAGGCGGACAAAGUUCAGUGUCGGGAAUUUUCCCCGUGACAUUCACUGGGGCAUGAGAUUUUGGAAGAAGUUUUUUACUUUGGUUUAGUCUUUUUUUCCUUCCUUUUUAUUCAGCUAGAAUUUCUGGUGGGUUGAUGGUAGGGUAUAAUGUGUCUGUGUUGCUUCAAAUUGGUCUGAAAGGCUAUCCUGCUGAAAGUCCUGCUUUCCUAUCUAGCAUUUAUUUCUCUGGCAAACUUUUCUUUCUUUUCUUUUUUAAAGUAAACUUGUGUAUUGAGUCUUAACUGUAUUUCAGUAUUUUCCAGCCUUAUGUGUUACAUUAUUCCAAUGAUACCCAACAGUUUAUUUUUAUUAUUUUUUUAAACAAAAUUUCACAGUUCUGUAAUGUAGGCACUUUUAUUUUCAUUGUGAUUUAUAUAUAAGGUAAUGUAGGGUUAUAUUUGGGAGUGACUGCAAGCAUUUUUCCAUCUGUGUGCAACUAACUGACUCUGUUAUUGAUCCCUUCUCCUGCCCUUUCCCAGGUAAUUUAAAUUGGUCAUGGUAGAUUUUUUUCAUAGAUUUGAAAAACUUUUAGGUUGUUACCAAGUAUGAAGUAUAAAUCUGGGGAAGAGGUUUUAUUUACAUUUUAGGGUGGGUAAGAAAGCCACCUUGUUACAAAUUUUUUAAUUUCCAAAAUAAUCUAUAUUAAAUGAGGGUUUCUGAUCUGUACUUUGUGUUUAGCUACCUUUUUAUAUUUAAAAAAUUAAAAAUGAAAAUUACGUUCUUACAAGCUUAAAGCUUGAUUUGAUCUUUGUUUAAAUGCCAAAAUGUACUUAAAUGAGUUACUUAGAAUGCCAUAAAAUUGCAGUUUCAUGUAUGUAUAUAAUCAUGCUCAUGUAUAUUUAGUUACGUAUAAUGCUUUCUGAGUGAGUUUUACUCUUAAAUCAUUUGGUUAAAUCAUUUGGCUUGCUGUUUACUCCCUUCUGUAGUUUUUAAUUAAAAACUUUAAAGAUAAGUCUACAUUAAACAAUGAUCACAUCUAAAGCUUUAUCUUUGUGUAAUCUAAGUAUAUGUGAGAAAUCAGAAUUGGCAUAAUUUGUCUUAGUUGAUAUUCAAGGCUUUAAAAGUCAUUAUUCCUGGGCUUGGUAAGUGAAUUUAUGAGAUUUACUGCUCUAGAAAGUAUAGAUGGCCAAAGGACCGUUUUGUAUUGCUUCCUGAUUACCAGUCUGAUUAUACCAUGUGUGCUAAUAUACUUUUUUUGUUAUAGAUUGUCUUAAUGGUAGGUCAAGUAAUAAAAAGAGAUGAAAUAAUUUAAAUUCUUAAAUGAAUCAGUUUUUCUUCCCUUUCUCCUUUCCGUCUUUCCUCUCUCUGUCCUUCCCCGAAAGUCUACUCGGGUGGGCAAAAAUGAAAAGGGGGAAAGUGAAUUAUGGGAUCGGUGUUUUGAAAGAGCAAUGUUUAUUUUCAGUGCUUUUCAGUUUGUCAAAGAGUGGAUCUCAAAAUCUUGCUUAAAGGGUAAUUGAGAUGUAGCAGAUUUAUUUACUUAGUCAUGGAAAGAAAAAAAUUCAGUCAAAAGCUAAAGAUUUCCUUUUGAUUGAAGACAGAUUGGUUCUGUGGCCUUGGAACUUUCCCAGACUUAAUGGGGAAACAUCAUUUCUAGAUUAGCAUACUCUUUGGUUUAAAUUUAAUAUAUACAUUUAAUGUUACUUAGGGAUACUUUUAUAUUUUGCAUAUAUAAAGCCUCAUAUAUAAAGCCUUAUUUCUGAUGCUCUUAGAUUUCUGAGGAGUGAGAUGAUUAAGUUGUAUUCAUUAGUGUAUUGGUAUUUCUUCACAUCCAGUGAAAUUGGAGAUAUGUUGUAUGUUAGAAGAGCAUUCUUUAAAUUGUGUUGCUUUGAACAUGUGUACCUUUUCUAGAUUCAGUAAUCCCUUCCCCCCGUCCUCUGGAGUAUGAAACCUUUAGAGUCACAAUAAAAUGUAACUAAAGAAAA